AAGAAGAGUGACUGUCUCAGUGCCGAGUGCCUCAGCAGCUUCUCCACAUGCUCUUCAGUCCCCAAAGUUGGAGAAUCCCAUCAAGGAGAGUAGCCCUGUAAGGAAUUCGAAUUUCCAGCAUUUUUCACCUCUGACAGAGCCCAGACACCAUGAACGCAAGUGAAUUCCGAAGGAGAGGGAAGGAGAUGGUGGAUUACAUGGCCAACUACAUGGAAGGCAUUGAGGGACGCCAGGUCUACCCUGACGUGGAGCCCGGGUACCUGCGGCCGCUGAUCCCUGCCGCUGCCCCUCAGGAGCCAGACACGUUUGAGGACAUCAUCAACGACGUUGAGAAGAUAAUCAUGCCUGGGGUGACGCACUGGCACAGCCCCUACUUCUUCGCCUACUUCCCCACUGCCAGCUCGUACCCGGCCAUGCUUGCGGACAUGCUGUGCGGGGCCAUUGGCUGCAUCGGCUUCUCCUGGGGCUGCUGCCUGGGGAGAGGCUCCAACCAGCCUAUCAGAUGUGUCCAGAGCCUUGGAGCAGGGGGGUCUCUGGAAAAGGGCCUAGCUCCUGCCUGCAAACCACCAGUCCCACCCUAUCUGGAGGCGGCAAGCCCAGCAUGCACAGAGCUGGAGACUGUGAUGAUGGACUGGCUCGGGAAGAUGCUGGAACUACCAAAGGCAUUUUUGAAUGAGAAAGCUGGAGAAGGGGGAGGAGUGAUCCAGGGAAGUGCCAGUGAAGCCACCCUGGUGGCCCUGCUGGCCGCUCGGACCAAAGUGAUCCAUCGGCUGCAGGCAGCGUCCCCAGAGCUCACACAGGCCGCUAUCAUGGAGAAGCUGGUGGCUUACUCAUCCGAUCAGGCACACUCCUCAGUGGAAAGAGCUGGGUUAAUUGGUGGAGUGAAAUUAAAAGCCAUCCCCUCAGAUGGCAACUUCGCCAUGCGUGCGUCUGCCCUGCAGGAAGCCCUGGAGAGAGACAAAGCGGCUGGCCUGAUUCCUUUCUUUAUGGUUGCCACCCUGGGGACCACAACAUGCUGCUCCUUUGACAAUCUCUUAGAAGUCGGUCCUAUCUGCAACAAGGAAGACAUAUGGCUGCACGUUGAUGCAGCCUACGCAGGCAGUGCAUUCAUCUGCCCUGAGUUCCGGCACCUUCUGAAUGGAGUGGAGUUUGCAGAUUCAUUCAACUUUAAUCCCCACAAAUGGCUAUUGGUGAAUUUUGACUGUUCUGCCAUGUGGGUGAAAAAGAGAACAGACUUAACGGGAGCCUUUAGACUGGACCCCACUUACCUGAAGCACAGCCAUCAGGAUUCAGGGCUUAUCACUGACUACCGGCAUUGGCAGAUACCACUGGGCAGAAGAUUUCGCUCUUUGAAAAUGUGGUUUGUAUUUAGGAUGUAUGGAGUCAAAGGACUGCAGGCUUAUAUCCGCAAGCAUGUCCAGCUGUCCCAUGAGUUUGAGUCACUGGUGCGCCAGGAUCCCCGCUUUGAAAUCUGUGUGGAAGUCAUUCUGGGGCUUGUCUGCUUUCGGCUAAAGGGUUCCAACAAAGUGAAUGAAGCUCUUCUGCAAAGAAUAAACAGUGCCAAAAAAAUCCACUUGGUUCCAUGUCACCUCAGGGACAAGUUUGUCCUGCGCUUUGCCAUCUGUUCUCGCACGGUGGAAUCUGCCCAUGUGCAGCGGGCCUGGGAACACAUCAAAGAGCUGGCGGCCGACGUGCUGCGAGCAGAGAGGGAGUAGGAGUGAAGCCAGCUGCAGGAAUCAAAAAUUGAAGAGAGAUAUAUCUGAAAACUGGAAUAAGAAGCAAAUAAAUAUCAUCCUGCCUUCAUGGAACUCAGCUGUCUGUGGCUUCCCAUGUCUUUCUCCAAAGUUAUCCAGAGGGUUGUGAUUUUGUCUGCUUAGUAUCUCAUCAACAAAGAAAUAUUAUUUGCUAAUUAAAAAGUUAAUCUUCAUGGCCAUAGCUUUUAUUCAUUAGCUGUGAUUUUUGUUGAUUAAAACAUUAUAGAUUUUCAUGUUCUUGCAGUCAUCAGAAGUGGUAGGAAAGCCUCACUGAUAUAUUUUCCAGGGCAAUCAAUGUUCACGCAACUUGAAAUUAUAUCUGUGGUCUUCAAAUUGUCUUUUGUCAUGUGGCUAAAUGCCUAAUAAACAAUUCAAGUGAAA